AGUUUGCUUCAUAGCUCUGUGAAGAAGCUGUGGCCCACACUGGGGUCCCCUCUUUUCCUAAAUCCAGAUGAACAGGUUUCUCUUGCUAAUGAGUCUUUAUCUGCUUGGAUCUGCCAGAGGAACAUCAAGUCAGCCUAAUGAGCUUUCUGGCUCCAUAGAUCAUCAAACUUCAGUUCAGCAACUUCCAGGUGAGUUCUUUUCACUUGAAAACCCUUCUGAUGCUGAGGCUUUAUAUGAGACUUCUUCAGGCCUGAACACUUUAAGUGAGCAUGGUUCCAGUGAGCAUGGUUCAAGCAAGCACACUGUGGCCGAGCACACUUCUGGAGAACAUGCUGAGAGUGAGCAUGCUUCAGGUGAGCCCGCUGCGACUGAACAUGCUGAAGGUGAGCAUACUGUAGGUGAGCAGCCUUCAGGAGAACAGCCUUCAGGUGAACACCUCUCCGGAGAACAGCCUUUGAGUGAGCUUGAGUCAGGUGAACAGCCUUCAGAUGAACAGCCUUCAGGUGAACAUGGCUCCGGUGAACAGCCUUCUGGUGAGCAGGCCUCGGGUGAACAGCCUUCAGGUGAGCACGCUUCAGGGGAACAGGCUUCAGGUGCACCAAUUUCAAGCACAUCUACAGGCACAAUAUUAAAUUGCUACACAUGUGCUUAUAUGAAUGAUCAAGGAAAAUGUCUUCGUGGAGAGGGAACCUGCAUCACUCAGAAUUCCCAGCAGUGCAUGUUAAAGAAGAUCUUUGAAGGUGGAAAACUCCAAUUCAUGGUUCAAGGGUGUGAGAACAUGUGCCCAUCUAUGAACCUCUUCUCCCAUGGAACGAGGAUGCAAAUUAUAUGCUGUCGAAAUCAAUCUUUCUGCAAUAAGAUCUAGAAGCCUGGGCCCUUGCUUGUUUUGACUCAGGCAGUAAAAAGCCUCCAUCACUCUAUUUGGCUCAUUUUAUAUUUAGUUCCUUCCCCAGUCAACAACUGACCACAUCUGCCUCUGCCUGAGCAUUAGGAUGCUCAAACAUCCUAUCUUUCUUCUUCUAUUCAUGCUUUUAUCCAUUCUUCUCUGUCCUGUCUUCCCUGCUCCAACUCUUUCUCUCAAUAUUCCUGAUUUUUUUUUCAAUAAAUUUCACAUGGUUAAAGCACACAGGCUCAAGACAGACCUUUUUUUCCCCCAUUAAUCUAGUUGCAGGGUCAACAUGAGCUUCCUUCCACACCGACACUAAACUGGGUGCAUUGUUUAAGCAUUCCAUAUUUAUGAAAGUAAAGGAGUCUCCAAGGGCAGAGACAACAAAGAGGAAUGCAAAGUAGGUAUUAAUCUUUUACAGGGUGUAAACGUGCAGGUACUUCUGACACCCCCCCUUUUCCAUCCCUACACACUCUUCCAUUUAUUAUGGCAUACAAAAACUCAACUCUUCUUUGGCUCUUGAGAGUUUCUAGUCUUCAGUAGUCCACUACUAACAUAAUGAUAAUAGUAUAAUGAUUCCUUAUUUGCUAUAUAUUGCAGCAGUUCAUAAUGCUUAAAUCAUUUUUUUCACACACAAUGUUACUGAAUCAUCUAUACAGGAUAGGAGGGCAAAUGGAAAUACUAAACGGUCCCUCAUAUAAGUGUUAUGUUCUUCAAGAUGUUUUCACAUACACGGUCUCAUCUGAUCCUCAGGAAAGAUCCCAGAGUGGUAGACAGGAAAGAUGGCAUCAUCCUUUUUUGCAAAUAAGGAAAUGUGACACAGAGAUGUUUUCUUUAUUCAUACUCCAUGUUGUUCCAAAUUUACCAAGGUUACAGAGCUACAGAGAGCUAUAGGCAGAUUCCACAACCAAAUCUGCAAGAUCUAAAUCUGAGCUGUUUCCACCACAAUGAAAGUAGCCAGAAUGGUUCUAAGAACUCUUAGAACAGUACAACAAGAAGUCAAUUUUACUGUAUAUAAAAUUUAAAAUUUCAACAUAUAUACACAUCAUG